UGGUACCUUGAGAGGCUCAGGCCAGCAGGAAAAUCAAGCUGUGCCAAUUGGGGCAAAACCCAGCAAUUCCUCAUGGCUGGAAACAAAAUGUUCUGUAGGCCUAGGAGACAACGCCUUUCCCAUUCCAGAAGAGCAGAGCUGCAGUUUCCUGUCAGCCACUUGGAACGCUGCCUGCGAGAAAGUCAGCAUGCCCGGCACCUGAGCUCAACCACACCUGUUUUCCUGGCUGGUGUUCUCGAGUAUCUGACAGCCAACAUCCUGGAAAAGGUGGGCAAGGAGGUCAAGAACAGCUGCAGGCUGUGCAUCACCCCAGAACACGUGAAGAGGGCACUGCAAAAGGAUGAGCAGCUCAGAUGGAUCUUGGAGUUGGAAGAUGACACCCACUCUCAAGUAGAAGAAAUGCCCCAAUCUGAGGAGGAAGAGGAGGAGGAGGAGGAGAAGGAGGAGGAGAUGGUGGUGCUGGUGGUGAUGGGGGGAAGGAGGAGGAGGAGGAGAAGAAGGAGGAGGAAGGAUUCCUGAGUUUCGGAGCCAUGCGGGACUUCAUCAGCAACCUCCUCCAGAUGCCAAAAUUCCCAUAGAUGAAAGACCCCAGGUUGCUUCCAUCUGCCCAAGCUAUUAAACUGUGUAAAUGCA